GCCCCAGAGACGUGAACUGUCGUUGCAGAGAUUGCGGGCGGCUGAGACGCCGCCUGCCUGGCACCUAGGAGCGCAGCGGAGCCCCGACACCGCCGCCGCCGCCAUGGAGUCCGAGACCGAACCCGAGCCCGUCACGCUCCUGGUGAAGAGCCCCAACCAGCGCCACCGCGACUUGGAGCUGAGUGGCGACCGCGGCUGGAGUGUGGGCCACCUCAAGGCCCACCUGAGCCGCGUCUACCCCGAGCGUCCGCGUCCAGAGGACCAGAGGUUAAUUUAUUCUGGGAAGCUGUUGUUGGAUCACCAAUGUCUCAGGGACUUGCUUCCAAAGCAGGAAAAACGGCAUGUUUUGCAUCUGGUGUGCAAUGUGAAGAGUCCUUCAAAAAUGCCAGAAAUCAACGCCAAGGUGGCUGAAUCCACAGAGGAGCCUGCUGGUUCUAAUCGGGGACAGUAUCCUGAGGAUUCCUCAAGUGAUGGUUUAAGGCAAAGGGAAGUUCUUCGGAACCUUUCUUCCCCUGGAUGGGAAAACAUCUCAAGGCCUGAAGCUGCCCAGCAGGCAUUCCAAGGCCUGGGUCCUGGUUUCUCCGGUUACACACCCUAUGGGUGGCUUCAGCUUUCCUGGUUCCAGCAGAUAUAUGCACGACAGUACUACAUGCAAUAUUUAGCAGCCACUGCUGCAUCAGGGGCUUUUGUUCCACCACCAAGUGCACAAGAGAUACCUGUGGUCUCUGCACCUGCUCCAGCCCCUAUUCACAACCAGUUUCCAGCUGAAAACCAGCCUGCCAAUCAGAAUGCUGCUCCUCAAGUGGUUGUUAAUCCUGGAGCCAAUCAAAAUUUGCGGAUGAAUGCACAAGGUGGCCCUAUUGUGGAAGAAGAUGAUGAAAUAAAUCGAGAUUGGUUGGAUUGGACCUAUUCAGCAGCUACAUUUUCUGUUUUUCUCAGUAUCCUCUACUUCUACUCCUCCCUGAGCAGAUUCCUCAUGGUCAUGGGGGCCACCGUUGUUAUGUACCUGCAUCACGUUGGGUGGUUUCCAUUUAGACCGAGGCCGGUUCAGAACUUCCCAAAUGAUGGUCCUCCUCCUGACGUUGUAAAUCAGGACCCCAACAAUAACUUACAGGAAGGCACUGAUCCUGAAACUGAAGACCCCAACCACCUCCCUCCAGACAGGGAUGUACUAGAUGGCGAGCAGACCAGCCCCUCCUUUAUGAGCACAGCAUGGCUUGUCUUCAAGACUUUCUUUGCCUCUCUUCUUCCAGAAGGCCCCCCAGCCAUCGCAAACUGAUGGUGUUUGUGCUGUAGCUGUUGGAGGCUUUGACAGGAAUGGACUGGAUCACCUGACUCCAGCUAGAUUGCCUCUCCUGGACAUGGCAAUGAUGAGUUUUUAAAAAACAGUGUGGAUGAUGAUAUGCUUUUGUGAGCAAGCAAAAGCAGAAACGUGAAGCCGUGAUACAAAUUGGUGAACAAAAAAUGCCCAAGGCUUCUCAUGUCUUUAUUCUGAAGAGCUUUAAUAUAUACUCUAUGUAGUUUAAUAAGCACUGUACGUAGAAGGCCUUAGGUGUUGCAUGUCUAUGCUUGAGGAACUUUUCCAAAUGUGUGUGUCUGCAUGUGUGUUUGUACAUAGAAGUCAUAGAUGCAGAAGUGGUUCUGCUGGUACGAUUUGAUUCCUGUUGGAAUGUUUAAAUUACACUAAGUGUACUACUUUAUAUAAUCAAUGAAAUUGCUAGACAUGUUUUAGCAGGACUUUUCUAGGAAAGACUUAUGUAUAAUUGCUUUUUAAAAUGCAGUGCUUUACUUUAAACUAAGGGGAACUUUGCGGAGGUGAAAACCUUUGCUGGGUUUUCUGUUCAAUAAAGUUUUACUAUGAAUGACCCUGGCAGAGACUCCUGUCAUCCUAGCAGUUUACUCUGCGUUUGUUGUAUCUAGACAGUCAACAACUGAGUUGUCGGUGUUUAACCUGAAUGCUUGUUUUUCAGAAGAGGACUGUUUGUGCCGGUAAGAAUGAUCAGGUAAGGCCAUGAAAGUUUUUGUUGGCGUUUUUGUUUUUGAGAUGGGGUCUUGCUUUGUUCCUUGGGCCAGAGUACAUUGGCUACUCACAAGUGGGCUGGUAGCUGGCUACAGCCCCAGACUCCUGGCUUAAGCCACCUCCUGCCUCAGCCACCCUGGCAGCUGGGACUACAGGCAUGCGCCAUCACACUUAGCUUGAAAGUUUUAAUUUACUAAGAAUAUACCUGUGUUUCCCCCCAUUUCCUGAUUUAAACAGUACUGGCUUAUAUAGGAACCCAUCAAAGUUAAAUUCCCCAAAUUUAAAUUUAGUAAAUUUAGUGGUUUCACCUUGGCAAAUCUGCAAUAGUUUCACCAGCUCAAAUUUCAUGCUUUUGUAAGCUGAGCUUAUGUUUGUGAUUUUAAUCCUUUAAGUACUACUGUGGUAACUAAUCAUUUUUUUGUUUUUUUUGGUGGUGUUUUUGUUUUUGUUUUGAGAUGGAGUCUCACUCUGUUGCCCAGGCUGGAGUGCCGUGGCGCGAUCUCGGCUCACUGCAACCUCUACCUCCUGAGUUCAAGCGAUUCUCCUGCCUCAGCCUCCCGAAUAGCUGGGAUUACAGGUGCCCACCACAAUGUCUGGCUAAUUUUUUGUAUUUUUAGUAGAGACGAGGUUUCACCCAUGUUGGCCAGGCUGGUCUCAAACCCCUGACCUCAGGUGAUCUGCCCGCCUCGGCCUCCCAAAGUGCUGGGAUUACAGAUGUGAGCCACCGCACCCAGCCAGGGACUAAUCUUUAAAGCAAAGUUUUAUAUAUUUUUACGUGAGUAAUGUUAUGUGUAGGUGUUCUAUUUGGCAAAAUAAAUCAGCCUUUUCUAUCA